ACAUUGACUUGCUGUCUGACACAACUGCUGAAAAUGUUGGUGAAAAGUGAGUCUCGAAGUGGUAGCUCACACUUGUAAUACCAGCACUUUCGGAGGCUGAGACGGGGAUCGCUCGAGGCCAGGAGUUCAAGAGCAGCCUGGGCAACAUAACGAGACCCCCAUCUCUACCAAAAAUUUAAAAAUUAGCCGGGCAUGGUGGCGCAAGCCUGUUGUCCCAGUUACUCCUGAGACUAAGGCAAGAGGAUCCCUUGAGUCCAGGAGUUCAAGGCUGCAGUGAGCUAUGAUUGAGCCACUGCACUCCAGCCUGGGUGACAGAGCAAGACUCUUAUCUACCUGUGGGAAAAAAAAAAGAAAAAAGUUUAAUAGAUCCUGAAGAGUUGGCCGGGCGCGGUAGCUCACGCCUGUAAUCCCAGCACUUUGGGAGGAUGAGACGGGUGGAUAACGAGGUCAGGAGUUCGAGACCAGCUGGGCCAACAUGGUGAAACCCCAUUUCUACUGAAAUUACAAAAAUUAGCCGGGCGUGGUGGCGGGCGCCUGUAAUCCUAGCUACUCAGGAGGCGGAGGCAGGAGAAUCACUUGAACCCGGAAGGCAGAGGUUGCAGUGAGCCGAGAUGGCACCAUUGCACUCCAGCCCGGGCGAAAGAGCAAAAACUCCGUCUCAAAAAAAAACAAAGAUCCCGAAGAGUCAGUCGUUCAUCCAAGAAGCCCUGACUGAGCUCUUAUUCUGUGCCAGACUCUGUUCUAGGUGCUAUGGAUGGAGCAGGGACCAGGACCUACAAACACGUGGAGCGCAUUCUAAUAUCUGUGAUACUCUGCAAAACUGUUAAAACAAAUCCUUGCGGCCGGGCGCGGUGGCUCACGCCUGUAAUUCCAGCACUUUGGAAGGCCGAGACGGGCGGAUCACGAGGUCAGGAGAUCGAGACCAUCCUGGCUAACACAGUGAAACCCCGUCUUUACUAAAAAUACAAGGAAAUUAGCCAGGCGUGGUGGCGGGUGCCUGUAGUCCCAGCUACUCGGGAGGCUGAGGCAGGAGAAUGGCGUGAACCUGGGAGGCGGAGCUUGCAGUGAGCCGAGAUCGCGACACUGCACUCCAGCCUGGGCAACAGAGCGAGACUCCGUCUCAAAACAAAACAAAACAAAACAAAACAAAAAUCCUUGCUACCACUGGCCCUAAAGCAGGAGGCAUAGGGCUGCGUGUGAGGAGUAGUCCAUUGCAUGGGCUUCCUCCAGUUUGGCUUUGGAUUUUUGAGCUCUCUGAAUUUGUUGUUUGUGUCCUUUGCACAGUGUCCCUCCCAGGUUGCACCCAUGCCUGCCCCUCAGGGUCCCCCACUCCCAGUGAAUUUCACACCAUGCAGCAUGUACUUUAAGCCAUACAUCUUACGUAUGUUCCAGACAUUUGGUAAAACGCCGUUUAUGUGUUUUUCAGUGACUCACAAACAUUUUAUUUACGUAAAUGAGGAAUGUACUCAGGCACCCUUCGUGAUACCUUGCCCUCAGCAGGCACUCAACAGCAAUAAUAACUUUCAUUCCUUUUGUGCUUCUCUUAACAGUUCGUGUUUAGUAGGAGCACAGUAGCUGUUUGGGGAACGACCUUAAGUGAAUAGAUGUCUGAAAUGCUGUGUGAAGUGGGGCGCUUAAUAGGUGGUGAGAUGGUUUUAGAACCAGGGUUUUCCCUCUUUGCUUCUUGACUCCUUAACCAGUUUUCAUUAGGAGACCCCUUUGGAGGUUUGCAGUCAGUCAGAGUUGAGUGCCUACUGAGUGUACUGAAUUAUGAAAUGAGCACAGUUCCCAUUAACCUGAAUUUUUUGCUCCCAAUAUUAAAGGUGGAAGAAGGUCCAUAUCUUUUUCUGUGGGUGCUUCAAGUGUUGUUGGAAGUGGAGGCAGCAGUGACAAGGGGAAGCUUUCCCUGCAGGAUGUAGCUGAGCUGAUUCGGGCCAGAGCCUGCCAGAGGGUGGUGGUCAUGGUGGGGGCCGGCAUCAGCACACCCAGUGGCAUUCCAGACUUCAGAUCGCCGGGGAGUGGCCUGUACAGCAACCUCCAGCAGUACGAUCUCCCGUACCCCGAGGCCAUUUUUGAACUCCCAUUCUUCUUUCACAACCCCAAGCCCUUUUUCACUUUGGCCAAGGAGCUGUACCCUGGAAACUACAAGCCCAACGUCACUCACUACUUUCUCCGGCUGCUUCAUGACAAGGGGCUGCUUCUGCGGCUCUACACGCAGAACAUCGAUGGGCUUGAGAGAGUGUCGGGCAUCCCUGCCUCAAAGCUGGUUGAAGCUCAUGGAACCUUUGCCUCUGCCACCUGCACAGUCUGCCAAAGACCCUUCCCAGGGGAGGACAUUCGGGCUGACGUGAUGGCAGACAGGGUUCCCCGCUGCCCGGUCUGCACCGGCGUUGUGAAGCCCGACAUUGUGUUCUUUGGGGAGCCGCUGCCCCAGAGGUUCUUGCUGCAUGUGGUUGAUUUCCCCAUGGCAGAUCUGCUGCUCAUCCUUGGGACCUCCCUGGAGGUGGAGCCUUUUGCCAGCUUGACCGAGGCCGUGCGGAGCUCAGUUCCCCGACUGCUCAUCAACCGGGACUUGGUGGGGCCCUUGGCUUGGCAUCCUCGCAGCAGGGACGUGGCCCAGCUGGGGGACGUGGUUCACGGCGUGGAAAGCCUAGUGGAGCUUCUGGGCUGGACAGAAGAGAUGCGGGACCUUGUGCAGCGGGAAACUGGGAAGGUACAGACUGCUGAGGAGGACCAUCCAAGGGGCUGCCCUUCUCACUGCUCUAGGCUUGAUGGACCAGACAAAUAGGAUGAUGGCUGCCCCCACACAAUAAAUGGUAACAUAGGAGACAUCCACAUCCCAAUUCUGACAAGACCUCAUGCCUGAAGACAGCUUGGGCAGGUGAAACCAGAAUAUGUGAACUGAGUGGACACCCGAGGCUGCCACUGGAAUGUCUUCUCAGGCCAUGAGCUGCAGUGACUGGUAGGGCUGUGUUUACAGUCAGGGCCACCCCGUCACAUAUACAAAGGAGCUGCCUGCCUGUUUGCUGUGUUGAACUCUUCACUCUGCUGAAGCUCCUAAUGGAAAAAGCUUUCUUCUGACUGUGACCCUCUUGAACUGAAUCAGACCAACUGGAAUCCCAGACCGAGUCUGCUUUCUGUGCCUAGUUGAACGGCAAGCUCGGCAUCUGUUGGUUACAAGAUCCAGACUUGGGCCGAGCGGUCCCCAGCCCUCUUCAUGUUCCGAAGUGUAGUCUUGAGGCCCUGGUGCCGCACUUCUAGCAUGUUGGUCUCCUUUAGUGGGGCUAUUUUUAAUGAGAGAAAAUCUGUUCUUUCCAGCAUGAAAUACAUUUAGUCUCCUCAAAGGGACUGCAGGUGUUGACAUGAGUUGGAAAGGGAACCCUGGGAUACGUGGCGUCCCCUCUAUUGGAACAGUCUGAGGACUGAAGGCAUUUGUCCCUGGAUUUAUUGGAGACGGCCCAGCUCCUCCCUCUGAAGGUGGUCACAUUCUGUUGACUCUCCAUACUCAGCCUCUCCUCCAGAAACAGAUCUGUUCCAGAACAUUCCAGCACUUUCUAUCUGGCCUCCUUGUCCCCACACUACGCCCCCCCACCCUCGCCAGGGCUUCCUCUAGUGACACUGUUAGAGCUAAUCUCUGAGACAGGGAAGGCAUUACUCACUUAAAACCCAGGCUGAGUCCUGGCCACCUGCUGGAUUGUGACAUAGGAGGUGGAAUCCACUGAACUGCUACUUCUGCACAGGCUCCUUCUCCUGGGGCUGUACCCAGGCCCAGCCCUGAUGGCUCACCCUGUCAGGCACCAGCUGCUCCCUCCUGGGCUCUCACCCACCUGCACAUCCUCCUUCCUAGCAUCACAUUACCUGCGUGUUUCCCCAGACAAAAGCACUUCCCAUUCUUGAACCUUGCCUACCCUGGGCUGAGCUGACGGCAAUAGAUUUAAUGACAGUGACUCCCAGGAAGGGGGUCCUGUGACUUUGCGCCUUAAUAAGAACAAAAGGUGGAAUUGGUGACCUAGGAAAACUGUUGAAUUCUAAAAAGAAUGAAGUUAGUUUCUAACCCUAGUUAAUGUUCCUUUUUUAUUUUUUGAGUCUUGCCCUGUCACUCAGGGUGGAGUGCGGUGUUAUGAUCUCAGCUCACUGCAACUUCCGCCUCCCGGGUUUAAGCGAUUCUCCUGGGUAGCUGGGAUUACAGGUGUGUCCCACCACACCUAGCACAUGGGCAUAUUUGUAAUAGAGACAAGGUUUUGCUAUGUUGGCCAGGCUGGUCUCGAACUCCUGGCUUCAAGUGAUCCACCCACCUCGGCCUCCCAAAGUGCUGGGAUUACAGGCAUGAGCCACUGUGCCUGGCCCCUUUAUUUGAUAAUUUACACAUACAUUUUUGUCCAAAACUCUUCUUUAUUUCAAGAUGAUGUUUCUGUGGCUAUGUGUGGUAUGUGGUAUAAAUCUCAAUCUAUGGUCA